GCGCUUCUUCCGGGUGGGGCCCCGGGCCGAGGCGAUGGCGCCCUGGGCGCUCCUCAGCCCUGGGGUCCUGGUGCGGACCGGGCACACCGUGCUGACCUGGGGAAUCACGCUGGUGCUCUUCCUGCACGAUACCGAUAAAAGUGCAGAUGAACUGCUGGCCACACACAGCCACUCAUGGAACCAACAUCUCCAGGCCUUUGCUCAGCCAGGAACACACUUCCCCACCUCCAACUGCACCCCAACCCCACCCACUCCUGUUCUACCCGGCCCAGCCUCACUGUGCUCUCCGGCCUCUCCAGAGCUGCGGCAAUGGGAGGAGCAGGGGGAGCUGCUCCUGCCCCUCACCUUCCUGCUCCUGGUGCUGGGCUCCCUGCUGCUCUACCUCGCUGUGUCACUCAUGGACCCUGGCUACGUGAAUGUGCAGCCCCAGCCUCAGGAGGAGCUCAAAGAGGAGCAGACAGCCAUGGUUCCUCCAGCCAUCCCUCUUCGGCGCUGCAGAUACUGCCUGGUGCUGCAGCCCCUGAGGGCUCGGCACUGCCGUGAGUGCCGCCGUUGCGUCCGCCGCUACGACCACCACUGCCCCUGGAUGGAGAACUGUGUGGGAGAGCGCAACCACCCACUCUUUGUGGUCUACCUGGCGCUGCAGCUGGUGGUGCUUCUGUGGGGCCUGUACCUGGCAUGGUCAGGCCUCCGGUUCUUCCAGCCCUGGGGUCAGUGGUUGCGGUCCAGCGGGCUCCUGUUCGCCACCUUCCUGCUGCUGUCCCUCUUCUCGUUGGUGGCCAGCCUGCUCCUCGUCUCGCACCUCUACCUGGUGGCCAGCAACACCACCACCUGGGAAUUCAUCUCCUCACACCGCAUCGCCUAUCUCCGCCAGCGCCCCAGCAACCCCUUCGACCGAGGCCUGACCCGCAACCUGGCCCACUUCUUCUGUGGAUGGCCCUCAGGGUCCUGGGAGACCCUCUGGGCUGAGGAGGAGGAAGAGGGCAGCAGCCCAGCUGUUUAGGGUUGCUGGAGGCCGGGCUACCGUCUUGUGCCUGAAAACCACGGGGCCUGUCCCCAGCUGGGGUGAGCGCUCAGAGGGCCUGGGGCCCUCACUCCUGCCCACGCCUCCCAGACCCCAGAACGGAGCUUCAAGUCAGACAGAUCCCUGCCUUGGUGGGCAGUUCUGCCUUCCAAGGAAGAAGGGGAAGAAAAGGACCUGUGGGUGGCUCAGGCCCAAGCAGACCCCGGGCUCCACCCCAGCCCCGCCCAGGCUGCUGCCAGUGCACACUUUUACAAAUUUAAUAUAAAGCAAGUCCAGUCUUAAAAAGA